GUUCCACUUGACCGCUCUAAGCCGCCGCGCAGCCUGCGUUUUCUCCGGUACAGGUUGAGGCUACUAAGGUACAUUUUGCUGGGCCAGGCUGGGCGGGUCCCCGGGAUGGGCAGCCCUCUCGACGAGCGGCGACGCCGUGGUUGAGUCUAGAAAGCUAGAGUUGCUGGACAGCUAUCGCGGGAGCGCGGAGGGAAGUGGGAGGUCUGGACGGAGUGUGCACGUGUUGGCAGUCUCGCUCCGCCGUCGGAGCCACCAGGUCAAACCUGUGCUGGCCCUGGCCAAAGAAACUUCUGCGGGUCAGGCUGCUGUUGCCGGUGCAGUUCCCAGUACUUCCUCUGGGGCGUUUUUCAAUAAAAGCCAAACGCCCUUGCUCAUUUUCAGGGAAAGACCUGUUUCCUCCUGCUCUUUCCUCUCCACGGAUACUCUCCCCACCACUAAAAGGGUUUAGUAUAAUCCUUUUGUAGGCCAGAAAGCAGAUUUUCACUUGGGAAGAGACGACCCGUAGUAUGGGAUGUGGUAUGAUACCAGCAACUGGUCUAUUAUAUCAUUUAAACCACAUGGCUAUCUAAAGAGGUAUUUGGCUAUUAUAAAUAAAAUAGUGAUGAACACGUGUACAGGUGUUUGUACGGACAUAAGUUGUCAUUUCUCUUGAGUAAAUACCUAAAAGUGGGCUUGCUGGAGUUUUACUACCCUUGGAUGCUGCUGUUGACAUGGAAAAGAUUGAGGAACAAUUUGCUAAUCUGCACAUUGUUAAAUGUUCCUUAGGAACCAAAGAGCCCACUUACCUUCUUGGUAUAGACACAUCAAAGACUGUCCAAGCAGGAAAGGAAAACUUGGUUGCUGUUUUAUGUUCUAAUGGAUCAAUCAGAAUAUAUGAUAAAGAAAGGUUAAAUGUACUACGAGAAUUUAGUGGAUAUCCUGGACUUCUUAAUGGAGUCAGAUUUGCAAAUUCCUGUGACAGUGUAUAUUCAGCAUGUACUGAUGGCACUGUGAAAUGCUGGGAUGCUCGAGUAGCCAGAGAAAAACCUGUUCAGCUCUUCAAGGGUUACCCUUCCAAUAUUUUUAUCAGUUUUGAUAUUAAUUGUAAUGAUCAUAUUAUUUGUGCUGGUACAGAAAAAGUUGAUGAUGAUGCAUUGUUGGUGUUUUGGGAUGCAAGGAUGAAUUCUCAGAAUUUAUCUACAACUAAAGACUCACUUGGUGCAUAUUCAGAGACACAUAGUGAUGAUGUCACUCAAGUACGUUUCCAUCCCAGCAAUCCCAACAUGGUAGUCUCAGGUUCAUCUGAUGGCCUGGUAAAUGUAUUUGAUAUUAAUAUUGAUAAUGAGGAGGAUGCACUGGUUACAACCUGUAACUCAAUUUCAUCAGUAAGCUGUAUUGGUUGGUCUGGGAAAGGUUAUAAACAGAUUUACUGCAUGACACAUGAUGAAGGAUUUUAUUGGUGGGAUCUUAAUCAUCUGGACACUGAUGAACCAGUUACACGUUUGAACAUCCAGGAUGUCAGAGAAGUAGUUAACAUGAAAGAAGAUGCUUUGGACUAUUUGAUUGGUGGCCUAUAUCAUGAAAAGACAGACACAUUGCAUGUUAUUGGAGGAACAAACAAAGGAAGGAUUCAUUUGAUGAACUGCAGCAUGUCAGGACUGACCCAUGUGACUAGCCUUCAGGGAGGGCAUGCUGCUACAGUCCGUUCUUUCUGUUGGAAUGUGCAAGAUGAUUCUUUGUUGACUGGAGGAGAAGAUGCACAGUUGUUACUUUGGAAACCUGGAGCUAUAGAGAAGACCUUUACAAAGAAAGAGAGUAUGAAAAUAGCAUCCUCUGUGCACCAACGAGUACGAGUUCAUAGUAAUGAUUCUUAUAAAAGAAGGAAAAAGCAGUGAUAAUGCAUUUGGCACUUUGUUUGGUAGGUUUUAUAGUUUCAAAUAGUCCUUCUUGUUUACUACCCAUGGUAGACAUGUUUAAAGCUUUAUGUAAAAACAAGCCAGUUAGCAAACAGUCCUGGAAAAAUAUGGUGAGAAUGGUUUAAUUCCGGUCUUCACAUAUUCUAAAAAAUUUUAAAGCCUCUAAGUAUAAAAUCAGUGAGUUGAAAGUAAAAUUUCUUAUUUAAAGAACCCAUCUGUUAAUGUAGUAAAUGUUGGCUUUAAAGAAAUAGCUCCGAUAAGGACUUUUUAGAAGGAAAUACUUGGUAAAACUUAAUAAAACAGGUGGUUGGCUGCAUUUUUUAAGCCCAGUUUUUUACAUUUUAAAUUGUCUUUAUUGUGUAUAAAACCAGAUUAGACUAUAUUCUUCAUCUGAGGAGCAUCUAUAUGUUUAAUACACCUAAUGUAUUAUGCUGGAGUAUUUAAAUGUAAGUAUUUUAAUGAGUAAAUAGAAUUAACCUUUUUUACAAAUGAAAUGAUAGGCAUCUAUGUAAAGUGAGAAAAAUAUGUUUCGUAAAUAUUUGCAUCUUUAAUAUUGUUAGUAAGUAGUAAACAGGUGUUUUGCUGAUUGAAAGGAAGUUAUCUUGGUAAAUUGAGACUCAAAGUGAAAUACAAAAAUGAAAAUAUUUAUAAUAGGACUCGACUUGGAGAAAUUGCUAUUCUUCCUGUUGUCCAAACCAUAAAUCUGAGGAUAACCUGGGCUUUUCUCUUUCCUCUUCUCCUAACCAGUUUUUCACCAAGUCCUGUGCCAUUUCACCUCCUAACGUCUGUCAGCUAUCCUUUUGCCUUUACCUCACCACUAUUACCCUAGAGAAGACUUUCAUUAUUUCUCAUCUGGAUUACCAGCUCGAUCUCUAAUCUGCUUCAGUUCAUCCUUCUUGCUACUUCUAGGCUAAACAUCAAAAACAGAUCUGGUAGGGGCGGGGAAAUGAGGGGGAAGAAACAAAAACGUGAUGGUGCCUCAUGCUGCUUAAAAUCUUCAGUACAUUGAUGUUUUGAUGGCGGACUACAUAAGCGUUAAAAAUUGUGUUUUUCAGAAUCUUUAAAAUAUAAGACAGUGCUAUCUAGUGAAUAAAAAAAUUAGUUUGAAAGAUAUCUGGAGAAAUCGCAUUCAUAAAACAAUUGGAAGUGAAACUAUUAAAACAAUAGGGCUUUUUAAAAUUAAAAAUAUUUAAAAUUCAAAAGUAAUUAAUAGUGUUGGAAGAUGUAGGUGAGAAAAUAUUCCUGAAAGUAGAACUGAAAGAGACAAAGAGAAAAGAUGAAAGCCACAGAAGAUAAAUACAGGGGUCAAAACCAGACUAACAGUUUUAGAAAGUGAAAAAAGUUAAAAAAGAAAUGGGGGCAGUGGGUUAUUAGAAAUAACAUAAAUGGCUGGUAUGGUUUGUCUGUGUCCUCACCCAAAUUUCAUCUCGAAUUGUAAUCCCCAUAAUCCCCAUGUGUCUAGGGAGAGACCUGGUGGGAGGUGAUUGGAUCAUGGGGGUGGUUUCCCCUACGAUGUUCUCCUGAUAGUGGGUGAGUUCUCACAAGAUCUGAUGGUUUUAUAAAGGGCUCUGCCCCUUUAACUCCUCACUCUUUCUCCUGAAGCCUUGUGAAGAAGGUGCUUUGCUUCCCCUUUGCGUUCCCCCAUGAUUGUAAGUUUCUUGAGGCCUCCCUGGCCAUGCUGAACUCUUCAGUCAAUUAAACACUUUCCUUUAUAAAUUA